AGCUCGCUGUUCGCUUCGCUGCCUGACAGCUGCCCUGCCGCCACCAGGCAGUCCCAGCUUCCCCAAACCAGUCUUCUGGCCUCUGUGGCGCCCCAGGCCCGCGGGAUUCAGGGAUUAGGAUCUGGAAGGGUUUGGUCCAAUCCCCUAUCCCUCUCAGCGUCCUGGGCUCACCUCCCCGGCAGCUUAGCGCUCCUCUUCCAAAACUGCUUGCUGUUCUCAGCGGCCAUUGCUCUGGCCGGGGGAAGUCCUUGUAGGCGGGCCAAGGGUUUGCCCGGCGAGAUGCCCCCAGACCCCGCAAUCUGAGGGCCAACCCAGGCCGCUUCCCCGCCGCCGGUCACCCGCUCCCAGCUCCUGGGGACGCCAUCUUGGAUGUGGGCACCCCUCCACCCAGCACCGCUGCCAUUGGUGAGCUGCGCAAGCCGUGGACGGGCCGACCAAUUGGGAGCCGGAAUCCUGCAGGCCGCUGAAGCCGACCGGUAACGUCAGGGGCUGGGCACACAGGUGGACGGGGAAGGCGGAGCUUGGACGAGCCGAGAGGCGGGGCUCAAAGUUCCUACCCGCGAGAGGGAAGAAGCAGCUUCCACACUAGCAUAUUUACCUGUCUGUCUCCAGUGCCAAGCUCAGCCCCCAGCACCUGUAGAUACACAAUAGAUGUCUGCUGAGAGGUGCUCUGGUAAAACAAGUAUAAAAUGAAUGUCAGGAUGUUCUCCCUCAUGGUGGGCAUCUUCUCUGUCCUUAAUACCACCCAGUUCUUCAUCUUUGACCUGAACCAGAAGACACACAUUUGCUAUGAGGCCAAGUUCAGCAUCUACGUGGACUCAAAGUCGGAGCUAGUCACUUGGACCCUGUUCCACAGGGCUAAUAUCAGCACUGGCCUCUCCCUCACCACCAUCAUCAUCGGCUGCUUCCUCUUUUAUUGUAUCCACAAGAAUAUCUACAUGGGGCUGCUGAUCUAUGCCAUGUGGAUCAUCACUUACGAGCUCAUCAACUUCUCCAUAGUCCUGCUCCUCAACGGGAUCAUCAAAGAUCACUUCAAGACGCUGAGUUAUUUGCACUGGAUCUUCCAAAUCUCACACAUGCUCCUGCACUUUUUCUGUCUGCCCUUCAUCGUCAAGCAUGCAUACAACCUUUACAAGGAAUCCCAGACUGUGGGCAGGAAACGCCGCCACAGGCUCUGCUCCACCAUUGCAGUGAACUCAUGACUACCUGUCCGUCUGGGAAUGUUGUACCGGAAGUUAAACUGAACCAUGCCAGAUGCCAGGAAAGGUGGGAGGGAAUGGUGUUCCUCAACAAUGGAACCCUCCCUACCCUGCCUGUCUUCUGUUGAUGCUGCUUGGUUUGUCAGGGCUUUUGAGUUUUACGCACUGAGGAAUGAUUCUCGGGAGAGGGCAGGUUGUGCGGAUCAAUUAUUUUACAGAUGUGUUGUGUGACUUGUUUUAGCAGUUAAUGAUAUGUGGCCUUGUGCUUACUUAACCAUC